CUGGAGCGCGGCGGUGAUGGCGGGGCCGGUGAAGGACCGCGAGGCCUUCCAGAGGCUCAACUUCCUGUACCAGGCCGCCCAUUGUGUCCUUGCCCAGGACCCCGAGAACCAGGCGCUGGCGAGGUUUUACUGCUACACUGAGAGGACCAUUGCGAAGCGGCUCGUCUUGCGGCGACCACUAUCCUCCUCCGCCCCCAGGGAUCCCUCGGUGAAGAGGACUCUCUGUCGAGGCUGCUCUUCCCUCCUCGUCCCGGGCCUCACCUGCACCCAGCGCCAGAGACGCUGCAGGGGACAGCGCUGGACCGUACAGACCUGCCUAACAUGCCAGCGCAGCCAACGCUUCCUCAAUGAUCCCGGGCAUUUACUCUGGGGAGACAGGCCUGAGGCCCAGCUCGGGAGCCAAGCAGAUUCCAAACCACUACAACCCUUGCCAAACACAGCCCACUCCAUUUCAGACCGCCUUCCUGAGGAGAAAAUGCAGACUCAGGGUUCCAGUAACCAGUGAUGGAUUCACCCCAUCUCCCAAAUAAAGUUUACUUGUUUUACAUUCCA